AACCGGCACAACACAACAAAAUGGCUGCCGCGCCGCUGGGCCCCUGAGGAAAGAGCCCGAACUUCUCCCGCUCUACCUCAGCCUGCGGGACUGCUCGGCUCGGCUUCUAGGCGAGACAGGGGCUCCCUGUGUUUCCCAGGCUGCAGUGCAGUGGCCAGUCACAAGGUUGAUCAUAGCACAUUGUAGCCUGGAGCUCCUGGGAUCAAGCAAUCCUCCUGCCUCAUCCUCUGGAGUAACUGGGACUGCAAGUAUACAUACCGUGCCUGACGAAAUAUCACAAUAUUUGGUUUUGAUGAACACCUGGCUUUAUUCUUGCAAUGAAGAAAGGUUCUCAACAAAAAAUAUUCUCCAAAGCAAAGAUACCAUCAUCAUCUCACUCUCCUAUCCCAUCAUCUAUGUCCAAUAUGAGAUCUAGGUCACUUUCACCUUUGAUUGGAUCAGAGACUCUACCUUUUCAUUCUGGAGGACAGUGGUGUGAGCAAGUUGAGAUUGCAGAUGAAAACAAUAUGCUUUUGGACUAUCAAGACCAUAAAGGAGCUGAUUCACAUGCAGGAGUUAGAUAUAUUACAGAGGCCCUCAUUAAAAAACUUACUAAACAGGAUAAUUUGGCUUUGAUAAAAUCUCUGAACCUUUCACUUUCUAAAGACGGUGGCAAGAAAUUUAAGUAUAUUGAGAAUUUGGAAAAAUGUGUUAAACUUGAAGUACUGAAUCUCAGCUAUAAUCUAAUAGGGAAGAUUGAAAAGUUGGACAAGCUGUUAAAAUUACGUGAACUCAACUUAUCAUAUAACAAAAUCAGCAAAAUUGAAGGCAUAGAAAAUAUGUGUAAUCUGCAAAAGCUUAACCUUGCAGGAAAUGAAAUUGAGCAUAUUCCAGUAUGGUUAGGGAAGAAGUUAAAAUCUUUGCGAGUCCUCAAUUUGAAAGGCAACAAGAUAUCAUCGCUCCAAGAUAUAAGCAAGUUGAAACCGCUUCAAGAUUUGAUUUCUCUGAUCCUAGUUGAAAAUCCAGUUGUGACCCUUCCUCAUUACCUCCAGUUUACCAUUUUCCACCUCCGUUCAUUGGAAAGUUUGGAAGGUCAGCCAGUAACCACUCAGGAUAGACAGGAGGCUUUUGAGAGAUUCAGUUUAGAAGAGGUAGAAAGACUGGAAAGAGACCUAGAAAAAAAGAUGAUAGAAACUGAAGAGCUUAAGAGCAAACAAACAAGGUUCCUUGAGGAAAUUAAAAAUCAAGAUAAAUUGAAUAAAUCAUUAAAAGAGGAGGCCAUGUUACAGAAACAGAGCUGUGAGGAACUCAAGAGUGACUUAAACACAAAAAAUGAAUUGCCCUUGUCUUGGUUUCUUGCAGGCCCUUUUCUGCUGAUUCUUUAUUCUUCCUUAAAGCUAAAACAGAAGACCAUAGAAUUAACACGAGCAUGUCAGAAGCAAUAUGAGCUGGAACAGGAAUUGGCCUUUUAUAAAAUUGAUGCUAAAUUUGAGCCACUAAAUUAUUAUCCAUCAGAGUAUGCUGAAAUUGAUAAAGCCCCAGAUGAAAGCCCUUACAUUGGCAAAUCCAGAUACAAGAGAAAUAUGUUUGCCACAGAGAGUUAUAUUAUUGACAGUGCUCAGGCAGUACAGAUCAAGAAGAUGGAGCCAGAUGAACAACUUAGAAAUGAUCACAUGAACUUGAGAGGCCACACACCACUGGACACGCAACUGGAAGACAAAGAAAAAAAAAUAAGUGCAGCACAAACUCGACUAUCAGAACUGCAUGAUGAAAUAGAAAAGGCAGAACAACAAAUUUUGAGAGCUACUGAAGAAUUUAAACAACUGGAAGAAGCUAUACAACUAAAAAAGAUUUCAGAAGCAGGGAAAGACCUUCUUUACAAGCAGUUGAGUGGUAGACUACAACUUGUAAAUAAAUUACGCCAGGAAGCUCUGGAUCUAGAACUGCAGAUGGAAAAGCAAAAGCAGGAAAUUGCCGGAAAGCAGAAGGAGAUUAAGGACCUGCAAAUAGCCAUAGAUAGCCUGGAUUCCAAAGACCCAAAACAUUCCCAUAUGAAGGCUCAAAAGAGCGGUAAAGAACAACAGCUUGACAUUAUGAACAAGCAGUACCAACAACUUGAAAGUCGUUUGGAUGAGAUACUUUCUAGAAUUGCUAAGGAAACGGAAGAGAUUAAGGACCUUGAAGAACAGCUUACUGAAGGCCAGAUAGCAGCAAAUGAAGCCCUGAAGAAGGAUUUAGAAGGUGUUAUCAGUGGGUUGCAAGAAUACCUGGGGACCAUUAAAGGCCAGGCAACUCAGGCCCAGAAUGAGUGCAGGAAGCUGCGGGAUGAGAAAGAGACAUUGUUGCAGAGAUUGACAGAAGUCGAGCAGGAGAGAGACCAGCUGGAAAUAGUUGCCAUGGAUGCAGAAAAUAUGAGGAAGGAGCUUGCAGAGCUAGAAAGUGCCCUCCAAGAGCAGCAUGAGGUGAAUGCAUCUUUGCAGCAGACCCAGGGAGAUCUCAGUGCCUAUGAAGCUGAGCUAGAGGCUCGGCUAAACCUAAGGGAUGCUGAAGCCAACCAGCUCAAGGAAGAGUUGGAAAAAGUAACAAGACUUACCCAGUUAGAACAAUCAGCCCUUCAAGCAGAACUUGAGAAGGAAAGGCAAGCCCUCAAGAAUGCCCUUGGAAAAGCCCAGUUCUCAGAAGAAAAGGAGCAAGAGAACAGUGAGCUCCAUGCAAAACUUAAACACUUGCAGGAUGACAAUAAUCUGUUAAAACAGCAACUUAAAGAUUUCCAGAAUCACCUUAACCAUGUGGUUGAUGGUUUGGUUCGUCCAGAAGAAGUGGCAGCUCGUGUGGAUGAGCUAAGAAGAAAACUGAAAUUAGGAACUGGGGAAAUGAACAUCCAUAGUCCUUCAGAUGUCUUAGGGAAAAGUCUUGCUGAUUUACAGAAACAAUUCAGUGAAAUUCUUGCACGCUCCAAGUGGGAAAGAGAUGAAGCACAAGUUAGAGAGAGAAAACUCCAAGAAGAAAUGGCUCUGCAGCAAGAGAAACUGGCAACUGGACAAGAAGAGUUCAGGCAGGCCUGUGAGAGAGCCCUGGAAGCAAGAAUGAAUUUUGAUAAGAGGCAACAUGAAGCAAGAAUCCAGCAAAUGGAGAAUGAAAUUCACUAUUUGCAAGAAAAUCUAAAAAGUAUGGAGGAAAUCCAAGGCCUUACAGAUCUCCAACUUCAGGAAGCUGAUGAAGAGAAGGAGAGAAUUCUGGCCCAACUCCGAGAGUUAGAGAAAAAGAAGAAACUUGAAGAUGCCAAAUCUCAGGAGCAAGUUUUUGGUUUAGAUAAAGAACUGAAGAAACUAAAGAAAGCCGUGGCCACCUCUGAUAAGCUAGCCACAGCUGAGCUCACCAUUGCCAAAGACCAGCUGAAGUCCCUUCAUGGAACUGUUAUGAAAAUUAACCAGGAGCGAGCAGAGGAGUUGCAGGAAGCAGAGAGGUUCAGCAGAAAGGCAGCACAAGCAGCCAGAGAUCUCACCCGAGCAGAAGCUGAGAUCGAACUCCUGCAGAAUCUCCUCAGGCAGAAGGGGGAGCAGUUUCGACUUGAGAUGGAGAAAACAGGUGUAGGUACUGGAGCAAACUCACAGGUCCUAGAAAUUGAGAAACUGAAUGAGACAAUGGAACGACAAAGGACAGAGAUUGCAAGGCUGCAGAAUGUACUAGACCUCACUGGAAGUGACAACAAAGGAGGCUUUGAAAAUGUUUUAGAAGAAAUUGCUGAACUUCGACGUGAAGUUUCUUAUCAGAAUGAUUACAUAAGCAGCAUGGCAGAUCCUUUCAAAAGACGAGGCUAUUGGUACUUUAUGCCACCACCACCAUCAUCAAAAGUUUCCAGCCAUAGUUCCCAGGCCACCAAGGACUCUGGUGUUGGCCUUAAGUACUCAGCCUCAACUCCUGUUAGAAAACCACGCCCUGGGCAGCAGGAUGGGAAGGAAGGCAGUCAACCUCCCCCUGCCUCAGGAUACUGGGUUUAUUCUCCCAUCAGGAGUGGGUUACAUAAACUGUUUCCAAGUAGAGAUGCAGACAGUGGAGGAGAUAGUCAGGAAGAGAGUGAGCUGGAUGACCAAGAAGAACCCCCAUUUGUGCCUCCUCCUGGAUACAUGAUGUAUACUGUGCUUCCUGAUGGUUCUCCUGUACCCCAGGGCAUGGCCCUGUAUGCACCACCUCCUCCCUUGCCAAACAAUAGCCGACCUCUCACCCCUGGCACUGUUGUUUAUGGCCCACCUCCUGCUGGGGCCCCCAUGGUGUAUGGGCCUCCACCCCCCAACUUCUCCAUCCCCUUCAUCCCUAUGGGUGUGCUGCAUUGCAACGUCCCUGAACACCAUAACUUAGAGAAUGAAGUUUCUAGAUUAGAAGACAUAAUGCAGCAUUUAAAAUCAAAGAAGCGGGAAGAAAGGUGGAUGAGAGCAUCCAAGCGGCAGUCGGAGAAAGAAAUGGAAGAACUGCAUCAUAAUAUUGAUGAUCUUUUGCAAGAGAAGAAAAGCUUAGAGUGUGAAGUAGAAGAAUUACAUAGAACUGUCCAGAAACGUCAACAGCAAAAGGACUUCAUUGAUGGAAAUGUUGAGAGUCUUAUGACUGAACUAGAAAUAGAAAAAUCACUCAAACAUCAUGAAGAUAUUGUAGAUGAAAUUGAGUGCAUUGAGAAGACUCUUCUGAAACGUCGCUCAGAGCUCAGGGAAGCUGACCGACUCCUGGCAGAGGCUGAGAGUGAACUUUCAUGCACUAAAGAAAAGACAAAAAAUGCUGUUGAAAAGUUCACUGAUGCCAAGAGAAGUUUAUUGCAAACUGAGUCAGAUGCUGAGGAAUUAGAAAGGAGAGCUCAGGAAACUGCUGUUAACCUCGUCAAAGCUGAUCAGCAGCUAAGAUCGCUCCAGGCUGAUGCAAAGGAUUUGGAGCAGCACAAAAUCAAGCAAGAAGAAAUCUUGAAAGAAAUAAACAAAAUUGUAGCAGCAAAAGACUCAGACUUCCAAUGUUUAAGCAAGAAGAAGGAAAAACUGACAGAAGAGCUUCAGAAACUACAGAAAGACAUAGAGAUGGCAGAACGCAAUGAGGAUCACCACCUGCAGGUCCUUAAAGAAUCUGAGGUGCUUCUUCAGGCCAAAAGAGCCGAGCUGGAAAAGCUGAAAAGCCAGGUGACAAGUCAGCAGCAGGAGAUGGCUGUCUUGGACAGGCAGUUAGGGCAUAAAAAGGAGGAGCUGCAUCUACUCCAAGGAAGCAUGGUCCAGGCAAAAGCUGACCUCCAGGAAGCUCUGAGACUGGGAGAGACUGAAGUAACUGAGAAGUGCAAUCACAUUAGGGAAGUAAAAUCUCUUCUGGAAGAACUGAGUUUUCAGAAAGGAGAACUAAAUGUUCAGAUUAGUGAAAGAAAAACUCAACUUACACUUAUAAAGCAGGAAAUUGAAAAAGAGGAAGAAAAUCUUCAGGUUGUUUUAAGGCAGAUGUCUAAACAUAAAACCGAACUAAAGAAUAUUCUGGACAUGUUGCAACUUGAAAACCAUGAGCUACAAGGUUUGAAGCUACAACAUGACCAAAGGGUAUCUGAAUUAGAGAAGACUCAGGUGGCAGUGCUAGAGGAGAAACUGGAGUUAGAGAAUUUGCAGCAGAUAUCCCAGCAGCAGAAAGGGGAAAUAGAGUGGCAGAAGCAGCUCCUUGAGAGGGAUAAACGAGAAAUAGAACGAAUGACUGCUGAGUCCCGAGCUUUACAAUCGUGUGUUGAGUGUUUGAGCAAAGAAAAGGAAGAUCUCCAAGAGAAAUGUGACAUUUGGGAAAAAAAGUUGGCACAAACCAAAAGGGUUUUAGCAGCAGCAGAAGAAAAUAGCAAAAUGGAGCAAUCAAACUUAGAAAAGUUGGAAUUGAAUGUCAGAAAACUGCAGCAGGAACUAGACCAACUAAACAGAGACAAGUUGUCACUGCAUAACGACAUUUCAGCAAUGCAACAGCAGCUCCAAGAAAAACGAGAAGCAGUAAACUCACUGCAGGAGGAACUAGCUAAUGUCCAAGACCAUUUGAACCUAGCAAAACAGGACCUGCUUCACACCACCAAGCAUCAGGAUGUGUUGCUCAGUGAGCAGACCCGACUCCAGAAGGACAUCAGUGAAUGGGCAAAUAGGUUUGAAGACUGUCAGAAAGAAGAGGAGACAAAACAACAACAACUUCAAGUGCUUCAGAAUGAGAUUGAAGAAAACAAGCUCAAACUAGUCCAACAAGAAAUGAUGUUUCAGAGACUCCAGAAAGAGAGAGAAAGUGAAGAAAGCAAAUUAGAAACCAGUAAAGUGACACUGAAGGAGCAACAGCACCAGCUGGAAAAGGAAUUAACAGACCAGAAAAGCAAACUGGACCAAGUGCUCUCAAAGGUGCUGGCAGCUGAAGAGCGUGUUAGGACUCUGCAGGAAGAGGAGAGGUGGUGUGAGAGCCUGGAGAAGACACUCUCCCAAACUAAACGGCAGCUUUCAGAAAGGGAGCAGCAAUUGGUGGAGAAAUCAGGUGAGCUGUUGGCCCUCCAGAAAGAGGCAGAUUCUAUGAGGGCAGACUUCAGCCUUCUGCGGAACCAGUUCUUGACAGAAAGAAAGAAAGCUGAGAAGCAGGUGGCCAGCCUGAAGGAAGCACUUAAGAUCCAGCGGAGCCAGCUGGAGAAAAACCUUCUUACAAUUAAUGAAGACUCAGAAAGGGAUAGUAGCUUAUUAUCAAAGGAGCAAAAACAGGAGAACAGCUGCAUACAAAAGGAAAUGGCAACAAUUGAACUGGUAGCCCAGGACAACCAUGAGCGGGCCAGGCGCCUGAUGAAGGAGCUCAACCAGAUGCAGUAUGAGUACACGGAGCUCAAGAAACAGAUGGCAAACCAAAAAGAUUUGGAGAGAAGACAAAUGGAAAUCAGUGAUGCAAUGAGGACACUUAAAUCUGAGGUGAAGGAUGAAAUCAGAACCAGCUUGAAGAAUCUUAAUCAGUUUCUUCCAGAACUACCAGCAGAUCUAGAAGCUAUUUUGGAAAGAAACGAAAACCUAGAAGGAGAAUUGGAAAGCUUGAAAGAGAACCUUCCAUUUACCAUGAAUGAGGGACCUUUUGAAGAAAAACUGAACUUUUCCCAAGUUCACAUAAUGGAUGAACACUGGCGUGGAGAAGCACUCCGGGAGAAACUGCGUCACCGGGAAGACCGACUCAAGGCCCAACUCCGACACUGUAUGUCCAAGCAAGCAGAAGUAUUAAUUAAAGGAAAGCGGCAGACAGAGGGCACUUUACACAGUUUGAGGAGACAAGUAGAUGCUUUAGGGGAAUUGGUCACCAGCACCUCUGCAGAUUCAGCGUCAUCACCCAGUCUGUCUCAGCUGGAGUCUUCCCUCACAGAGGACUCUCAACUUGGACAAAAUCAGGAAAAGAAUGCCUCAGCCAGAUGAGGAAUACUGUCUUGUGUAAAUAUAUUCAAGGAAAACACCUCCACUACCUCACUGACUUCAUAAUUGGAAUGUCACAUGGUUUUUUUAAUCAAGAUGCAGUGAACUGAGAUUCUGAAACUCCACUGUAGUUUACUUUGCCUGUACCAUUAAUGCCAAUGUUUUUAUAAAUCACUUGUACAUAGUACAUAUGGGAAUAGUUGCAUAUGGGAAUUUAAACCAACAUGUGGCUGAGCCUUUUUUUUUUUAAUCUUCGUAACAUGUUUAAAAAAAAACAGUGAUUUUAACUGCAUAUUUGAACCUACAAACUGGUAAAUCUUAUUAACAAAAAGAAUGUACUUAAGGCCCUCUUUAUUUAUAGUGUCGAGUUAUUUUUGAAUUUUGCUUAAAAUCUAUUUUUCAUAUGAAAAUAAAAGAUAACAAUCAA